AGUUGCGCGCGUGGCUCUGGCUGCGCAGGAACAGCUGGUGCCUCCGAGGGCGGUCGGCGAGCGCGCGGGCGUGGGGCGCUGGGGGGCCGGUCGGGCAGCGCUGCGGGAGCAGCCGCCGGCACCGCCGCCUUGCACCAUCGCAUCAUGUCCGGGCAGCUGGAGCGUUGCGAGCGCGAAUGGCACGAGCUGGAGGGAGAAUUUCAAGAACUGCAGGAGACGCACAGGAUCUACAAGCAGAAGCUGGAGGAGCUGGCUGCGCUGCAGACGCUGUGUAGCAGUUCCAUCAGUAAGCAGAAGAAGCACCUCAAGGACUUGAAGCUUACACUCCAGAGGUGCAAACGCCAUGCCAGUCGGGAGGAGGCGGAGCUCGUUCAGCAGAUGGCAGCGAACAUCAAGGAGCGGCAGGACGUCUUCUUCGACAUGGAGGCCUACCUGCCCAAGAAGAACGGGCUCUACUUGAACCUGGUCCUCGGCAAUGUGAACGUGACCCUCCUCAGCAACCAGGCCAAGUUCGCCUACAAGGACGAAUAUGAGAAGUUCAAGCUCUACCUGACCAUCAUCCUGCUCCUGGGUGCCGUGGCAUGUCGAUUUGUCCUUCACUACAGGGUGACUGACGAAGUCUUCAACUUCCUGCUGGUGUGGUAUUACUGCACCCUGACCAUUCGGGAGAGCAUUCUCAUCAGCAACGGCUCAAGAAUUAAAGGCUGGUGGGUGUCUCACCACUACGUCUCCACAUUCCUGUCCGGAGUGAUGCUGACCUGGCCUAAUGGACCCAUUUAUCAGAAGUUUCGCAACCAGUUCUUAGCAUUUUCCAUUUUUCAGAGCUGCGUCCAGUUCCUGCAAUAUUAUUACCAGAGGGGCUGCCUCUACCGGCUGCGGGCCCUGGGGGAGAGGAACCACCUGGAUCUCACAGUGGAAGGGUUCCAGUCCUGGAUGUGGCGGGGCCUCACCUUUCUCCUGCCCUUCCUCUUCUGUGGCCAUUUCUGGCAGCUCUACAAUGCCGUCACGCUGUUUGAGCUCUCCAGCCACGAGGAAUGCAGAGAAUGGCAGGUGUUCGUACUGGCGUUCACCUUCCUCAUCCUCUUCCUCGGCAACUUCCUGACCACGCUCAAAGUCGUGCAUGCCAAGCUCCAGAAGAACAGAGGCAAGACAAAGCAGCCGUGAGCCUCGGGCUCCUGUGCCCUCGGCCCGGACUUCAGACUGCAGGGGGCUCCCGGGCUCCUUCCCAGCAGCCCUCUCAGGCCCGUGGCAUCGCUGGGAGAGGGCCCAGGCCCUGGUCCCCCAGUGGACCCCAGUGGUCUAGAGGAAUGUGAGCCCCGCCUGUCCGCACAGUGUCCGCCCACCUAUUUAUGACAUAUUUAAUGCUGGGUCCCCCAUCGUCCCUGGAACCCGAGGCCUCACUCCUGUGCUUGAAGGUGGCUGAGGCCGGGCCAGUCUUCCUGGGGAUGGGGCCUGAAGCCUCAGGGAGCCCCUCUGUUCCCACUCCUGUCAUUUGAACCCCUCUGGGUGGGGUUUGGAUGUGCCUCGCGGGGUUGGAUUUAUGCUGACCUGCUACUUACCAGGCCCAGGCUGGGGUGGUGUGAACCCUCAGUGUCCUGUGGCGCCCCCACCCCGGGGCCACUCUGCUUCUGCUGUGAGCCCCCUCCUCGCCCACCCCGCCACGUGGUGAGGGUUAUUUUAAGUUCUCAGAGACCCACCGCGUCUGCCUCGUGCUCUUCUUGCCCCUGGAGCGCUGGGGGCAUCCUGAGUCAGGCUGUGAGAAGAUUCGCCACCAGAGGGCGCCCCGGGCCCUGGGUCGUCCAAGGGGACAAGGACGUUCCCGUCUGUGCUUCGGGGUUCCCUGACCCCCCCAUCCUGCAGCCCACCUUCCUGCAGUGUCGUGGCAGGUACUUGGAGAGUGGGACCAAGACCCUUGGCCCCUGUGGAGGGGAACCACCUCCCCCCUCCUUCCCAGAGCUUCUGGAUGUUGUGGGAGGGAGGUGGGGGUGCCUGGCAGGCUCACCCCCAGGGGCCGCACCCUGAGGCGGGGUCAGAGCCACUGGGCAUCGCUUGGGUGAGAUUCUGCAUUCGACGGGAGGCAGAGAGGCCACCAGGUUUGGCUGAGUGCUCUGCCCCACCAUUCAUAUAUGGGCCUCAGCUCCCCCUAACUGUGGCCCUACAAAUCCCUAGGCCAGACCUCACAGCAGUGCCCACAGGCAUGCCUUGUUUAGCCCUCCUCAAGGAAUUUUAAAAUUUUUAAUUACUUUUUUUUUUUUUGAGACAGGGUCUGUUGCCUAGGCGGGAGUGCAGUGGCAUCAUAGGUCACUGUAGCCUCCGCCUCCAGGGCUCAAGGGAUCCUCCCACCUCAGCCUCUGGAGUAGCUGGGACCACAAUCACACACCACCAUGCCCUGCUCCUUUUUUUUUUUUUUUUUUGAGAUGGGAGUCUCGAUCUGUUACCCAGGCUGGAGUGCAGUGACACAAUCUCAGCUCACUGCAACCUCUGCCUCCCAGGUUCAAGUGAUUCUCCUGCCUCAGCCUCCCGAGUAACUGGGACUACAGGCGCGUGCCACCAUGCCUGGCUUUUGUUUUGUUUUGUUUUGUUUUGUAUUUUUAGUAGAGACAGGGUUUCACCAUGUUUGCCAGGAUAGUCUCGAUCUCUUGACCUUGUGAUCUGCCUGCCUCAGCCUCCCAAAGUGCUGGGAUUACAGGUGUGAGCCACCAUGCCUGGUCACCCUGCUACUUUUUAAUACUUUUUAGUAGAGAUGGGGUCUCACUAUGUUGCCCAGGCUGGUCUCCAACUCAUGGGCUCAACUCAUCCUCCUAUCUUGGCCUCCCAAAGCGCUGGGAUUACAGGUGUGAGCCACUGUGCCUGGCCUGAUUACAUUUUUAAAAUGAGAUUUCCCCACCCCUACAGUGAGAUUCCACAUAAAAAUCCAGAUUUCUGCUUUCCCUAGAAAAACGGACCUGGCAACAUUCCCGUGGCACAGGACGCCUACUCUCCAGUUGCCACAGGCCCUGCCACCCCCCUGCCCUUCAUUCUGGUCUCCUUUCUGGUCCUUUUUAGGCACCUGCGUUUGCCCUAGAUUAGGAGUCAGCUAGCUGUCUGUAAAGGGCCAGAUGGCAACUAUUUUGAGCUUUAUGGGCCAGGUGGUUUGUGGCAGCUACUCUUCACCUGCAGCCCCAGAGCACAAGGCAAUGCAGAAAGGAAUGGGUGUUGCUGUGUUCCAAUAAAACUUUAUUUACAAAUCAGGCUGUGGCCAGAUGUGGCCCACAGGCUGUAGUUGUUGGACCUCUACCGUAGACCAUCAUGAGGCCUGGGGUUCUUCGAGAACAAGAACUCCUUGGUUGAUUCCCCAGGGUACGGCAGGGCCUUGGGAACCUGGGUGGGUUGGGGAGGGUCUCAGAAGGCUCCUUCCUUUGGCAACCUGACUUCUUGGAAGCUCAGGUUUAGCUGACGCCCCAGCACUGGGCCAGGGGGGCUGAGGCAGGAGAUAUGGGGAAGGCUAGGAGUUGCCUGAAGCCAUUAUCCCAUCUUAGGCGACACCGACUCCUAGGCGCCCUCCAGAGCCAAGCAGCUUGCGACUUCUGGUAGGCACCGGAAUCCCCUGGGAUGCUUGUUUUAAAAGUCCUGGGCCGGGCACGGUGGCUCACGCCUGUAAUCCCAGCACUUUGGGAGGCUAAGGCGGGUGGAUCACGAGGUCAGGAGUUCAAGACCAGCCUGGCCAACAUGGUGAAACCCUGUCUCUACUAAAAAUACAAAAAUUAGCCGGACGUGGUGGUGUGCGCAUGUAGUCCCAGCUACUCAGGAGGCUGAGGCAAGAGAAUCGCUUGAACCCAGGAGGUGGAGCUUGCAGUGAGCCAAGAUCAUGCCACUGCACUCUAGCCUGAGUGACAGAAUGAGACUCUGUCCCAAAAAAAAAAAAAAAAAAAAAUUCCCAGACCCUCGGCCCCAGACCUUCCCAAAGGAGGCUCAGGGAUUAGGUAUCUGGCUGUUGGUGACACAGGUGGUCUAUGAACCAGUUCUGAGAAACUGUCCCGCGUGGACAGGGGGUAGAUCCCAUCAGUUCUCAAAGGAGGCCAGGAUGUCUCGCCUCCUGAACUCCACAGGCUGGUAGAAGCGGGGCUUGAGGGACAGCAGGUUGGGAGCUUGAGGACUAAGUGGGCCAGUCCUGUCCUACCACAGUGGGGGGAACAGUCCACAGAAAACUUGCUCAUGACCACACUGGGAGCCGACUGUUCUUCCCAUCCCAAGUCUCUGACACUGGGGGCUUUGGGUGAAACCUUAAGGAGAUGGUCAGAUGGGUGGUCCAGGGUAUACUUUUAACAACUGAGAAGCCAUUUUUUCUGCCCCCUGGGCACAUGUGCCCAGCUCUGCAAAGACAGUGGCCAAGUUGAAGACAAGUCUUCCAUGUGGGGUGGAGAUGGGAGGGGUGGGUGCCAGGCUGCAGCCUGUGUCCUCCUGAUAGGCCCAGCCCCCUCGGUGGCCUCCGUGUUCCUGGGGGAAGGAAGGAAGGAGCUGGAGGAUACAGUGGUGCCUAUCUCGGGAGCCCAGGGAGGCAGGGACACAGGAGUGGCAGGCUUGGGGCGCCCGCGUGGAACAGUGCCAGGUCUACGUUUACCCACUACCAGAUAGACUUUUUCAUUUCAAGCAUAACUUGAGUCUGCACUGGGGAGACACUCGUGGUGGGGGUGGCUGUGAUGAGGGCACUUGCGAGUCCCGACAACAGACACUGGCUCCUGCACCCACAUCACCACCAUGUCCCAGGGGCAGCCUGGAGGGGAGUUUGUGGUCAGAGCCCCAGCCAGGAAAGGAGAGAGUUCCAGAAUGUUCCAAGAGUCUAGCCGCAGGCCCCAGACACCAUGAGCUGGAGGGUCGGGAUGGGGCAGCCUCCCUGGUGCAAUCGGCACCUGGGCCCCCGGGCCCUGUCAGUGCUGUCGUGAGGUCUGUCUGCCCUGGGUCAGAGCAGCAGGCAGAGCCGGCGCUUCUUCUGCCGUUGCGCCUUCUUCAGAGCGCUGAGAGCCACCUUGGCGGCCUCCCGGAAGACGUCCUCCACAUUCUCCCGAAACUUGGCGGAACAUUCCAGGUAGAGAGCAGCUCGGAUCUGUUCGCAGGCGCUCAGGCCCUGGGUGGGGGGAGGAGCCAGCAUUAGGUGAGGGGCCCCUGGAGGUCUCCUAGCACCACCUGGUGGGUUUGGGACUGGCUCUGAGGACUCUGCAGGGAUGGAGGCCUUGGUUUGGGCCUGUCUGUCUCCUCCAUCCUGGCUGCCCCUCACAGUGUGUGGGUGGAAUGGAGGGCCAGGGCAGUGCAGCCCGCAGGUUGGAAGAAGCCCUGUCCAGGCCCCCACCCUGGCCUCUCUCCAGCUCCGGGCAGGGAGGGGCUGAAUCCUGAGACCCGGGGUUGGUUCCCCCAGGUGUCUCCCAGGCCUGUGAGAAGAGUUGGAGGCCUCAAGACAGAAAGGACUUCCAGCCACCUCUCUCCCUUCUCUGAAAGUACCAUUUAGGCAAAUUAAUUUGCCCUUUUAUUUAUUUAUUUUUGAGAUGGAGUUUUGCUCUUGUUACCCAGGCUGGAGUGCAAUGGCGCGAUCUUGGUUCAUCACAACCUCUGCCACCCAGGUUCAAGCGAUUCUCCUGCCUCAGCCUCCCGAGUAGCUGGGAUUACAGGCAUGCGCCACCAUGCCCGGCUAAUGUUGUAUUUUUAGUAGAGAUGGGGUUUCUCUCAUGUUGGUCAGGCUGGUCUCAAACUCCCAACCUCAGGUGAUUCGCCCGCCUCGGCCUCCCAAAGUGCUGGGAUUACAGGCGUGAGCCACUAUGCCCGGCCGGAUUUGCCCUUAUUAAUGGUUAUUUCUUGUGAAAGUUUCUUUUUGCCUUUGCAUUCCUUUUAUUCUGUUUAUUCCCCCAUGCCUCACCCAAAGAGUUGCACGGUCAAUUGGCCCGUGAAGGGGACGCCUACUUUCAAACAAGGCAGACAGGACACGACAGGACGGCGGCUCAUAGCACAGACUUUGGAUUGCAGUGGAUGGGACCAGAUCCUGGCUCCACUUCUCGCUAGCUGUGUGGCCCUGGGCAAGCUGCUUAACCUCUCUGGGCCUCAGUUUCUCCCCCUGUAAACUGGGGGAUGUGAACAGCGCCUGCCUCCGAGUCCUAAGGAUUGGGAGUAGUCGUGUAAAGUGCUCAGGUCCACAGGCCAUCAAUACUAAUAGUUAAAAAUUAUUCUUAGAAUCUUGCUUCCCUCAGCUCCCUGAAAGGCCACUAAGGCACCCCAGUUGCAGAGGCCAAAGGUCCGGGAGGCUUCACAGCCACGGCUGUGCCCCAGGGUCUUGGCCCCGGCCCACCUGCAUGUAGGUGAUGGGCUCCAGCUGGGCGGCCCGGAGCUUCCGCAGCUGCUCCUUGUCCUUCCUCAGGUCUGUCUUGCAGCCGAUGAGCACCAUGGGGAUCCCGCGGCAGAAAUGCGUGACCUCAGGGAACCACUGUGGAGGGAGGAGGCGGGAUCAGGGGUGCGGCCGGGCCCAGAUGUGGGGCCACCACCCAGGAGGCCGGCCUCACCUUGAUGAGGACGUUGUCGUAGCUGGUGGGAUUCAUGACGUCAUAGCAGAUGAGCACGAGGUGGGUGUUCUGGUAGGACAGGGGCCGCAGCCGGUCAUAGUCUUCUUGCCCUGAAAGCACAGAGCAGCGGGGGUCAGGGGACGUCCCCUCCCUGUCUGGACUCUGACGGGUGAAGGGGAAGGGGCCAGGCAAGUGACCCUGCCUUAGGGCCUCAAUUUCCUCAUCUAUACAAUGGGCAGCAAGCCAGGAGUGCUGGCACAGGCCUGUGGUCGCAGCUACUCGGGAGGCUGAGGCCGGAGGAUCGCUUGAGCCCAGGAGGUCAAGGCUACAGUGAGCCGUGAUCAUGCCACUGCACUCCAGCCUGGGUGACAGAGCGAGACCCUGUCUCUUAACAACAAAACCCAUGAGCGGCAGCCCCCCAGUCCUGGAUGGUGGUAAAGAAUCCUCAAGAUCAAACCCACGCAGUGCUGAGAGCUUGGCCUGAUUCUAGGGCUGGGGCUGGAGAAACUGCUAGAGAUGAUGCCGAUAGCCAGUGUGAUCCCCCUGCCCUGAUGGUCAAGGGCAGAGUGCAGACUGGAACCCUCCCCUCCCCAAAGAUUCAGACCUGUGGGGCUGAGUGGGCUCAUAGUGUCCCCAAGUCCUGAGAGGCUGGUGUCUGGCUUCAGCCUCCAGCUUCUCAGGUUCUGAUGCAGUCAGCUGAGUUCCCUGCCUAUUCUUGCAAGCACUAGGAGGAGGGUGGUGGGUUGCUGGGAACAGCACCGAGCGCCCUCCCCACCCAGAUUCACAGAGCACACUCCCUGGGGGGAUACUUUAAUCCGGAGGCCGUGACGCCUGGCUCCGCCCCGAGACGAGCUGAAUCCAAAUACGGAUCUAGGCUUGAGCUUGGUUGGGUUUGCUUUUUUCUUCUUCUUCUUUAUAAACAAUUCUUUGUAACUUUUUGUAUUGACAGUUUCAAACUUACAGUAAAAUUGCAACACGAGUAUGAA